GAACUAUUCAUGAAGCUUCUGAGUUCAGCGUGGGAGUGGGGAAGGGAGAGAGCUACCAACCACUCUCCUUUUGUGGGAAGAGGUUGAUAAAAACAGAGGCUGCCAAGAGAUGUACUUGAGUAGGAGGAGACUGCCCUGGCAACAAGUGAAUGUAGCCUUGGAUAUCCGCUCUCAGAAGGAAUAUGACAAAUCUGAAGCUAUACCUGAGGAAUUAGCUGGAGCUGGACAACAGUAACGAGGUGCAAGUCCCCAUGGAAGAUUCAAGCCUGUCCAGUGGUGUUGAUGUGGACAAAGGCUUUGCCAUUGCCUUUGUUGUUCUUCUGUUUCUGUUCCUAAUAGUGAUGAUUUUUCGGUGUGCCAAGCUGGUGAAGAAUCCCUACAAGGCCAGCUCCACAACCACAGAACCAUCUCUGAGCUGAAGUAUAAUAAAACCUGGUAGACUCCCCCAAGCAAGAGAUUUGAAAUCUGUUAUACACACUUUAUAUUAUUUCACCUCCCUGUUUCUCAGCCUUCUCACUCUUGCAUUCCACAGUGAGAUGAAACACAAGCCAGUUUGUAUUGUUCCUGUUCAGGGAAAUGGCUACUAAAGUGAGAUAAAGGUUGAAUUUAUUGGCUAGAAUAAGGCCAUAGAUUUUAAUUCUUCAGUGCCUAAGGUCCUUAGGAUGAGACAGUGGGCCAUAAUUUUAUGAUGUAAUGUAACAUAAUGUCAUCAUGCUUGGUAAGGUCCACCUGAAACUAGAAGCUCACCUAGAGGUGGCAGACUUGAAUGAUCCCUUUAGUUAUGCAAAUGUAGGCUCAGCAGAAACCAAAUGUCCUAUAAGAAGAGUGUAACCAGAUUGUUUUAGUGUGUGAAGUUUUAUAAAAUCUGCUGUUCUUAAGUGGGCAGAACUCUCUGGUAGAAGGGGACUAAUUUGCUGUGGGUGAAUUCCUUAAUCUCUCUCAUCCCAAAUUUCCUCAUCUAUAAAAUAAUAUGUAGAGGUUUCAGUGAGGGCCCCAGAAAAGAUAUAUCCGUGUCCUAACCCCUGGAAUGUGAGCUUAUUUGGAAAAAUGGUCUUUGCAAAUAUAAUUAAGAAUCUCAAGAUAAAUUCAUCCUGAAUUAUCUAGGUGAGACUUAAAUCCAAUGACUCCCCUAGAGAUUCUGGUACCCCAGUAUGGUCUUACUAACACCUUGAUUUUGGACUUCCGGCCUUCACAACUGUGAGGAAAUAAAUUUCUGUUGUUUUAAGGCA